GUGCGCUCUUCAGGACAGCAGAGGUCGGUUGGAGGUCUGCAUUCUCUGCCGACUUGGGCCCCAACUUCCCCAUCAGGUCACUGCUCCCUCCUCUGAGGUCUGGACAAAGGACAAGGCUGUAGGGACCUAGACUGUCCUAGACGGGGAGGACAUCUAUCCUCAGUGGUCUUUCCAGCAGUUUGUUUGGAGCUGCUCAUCCUGAUCUUUUGGCUGACUCUGGCAGAGGGAAAGUCAGAUUUGAGGCCUGAGCUCUAACAGGCAUCCAGAGAGGAAGGAAGGGCCCACCCCGUGACAUCAGUGAAACGGAAGCACCCUGCAGGUGACAUCACUGUUGCUCAGGGCAACGCCUCCACCCUAAGGCGGACGGGGAGGUGAAAAAUCGGCCUCAAGUGUGAGACGCAUGUUGAAGGGAAGGGACAUAGAAGGUGUAACGUUCACAGGAAAGCUCCAACCAUGGCCAUGGGGCUCUUCCGCGUGUGUCUGGUGGUGGUGACGGCCAUCAUCAACCACCCGCUGCUGUUCCCGCGGGAGAACGCCACAGUCCCCGAGAACGAGGAGGAGAUCAUCCGCAAGAUGCAGGCGCACCAGGAGAAGCUGCAGCUGGAGCAGUUGCGCCUGGAGGAGGAGGUGGCUCGGCUGGCGGCCGAAAAGGAGGCACUGGAGCAGGUGGCGGAGGAGGGCAGGCAGCAGAACGAGACACGCGUGGCCUGGGACCUCUGGAGCACCCUCUGCAUGAUCCUCUUCCUGAUGAUCGAGGUGUGGCGGCAGGACCACCAGGAGGGGCCCUCACCUGAGUGCCUGGGCGGUGAGGAGGAUGAGCUGCCUGGGCUGGGGGGCGCCCCCUUGCAGGGCCUCACCCUGCCCAACAAGGCCACGCUUGGCCACUUUUAUGAGCGCUGCAUCCGGGGGGCCACGGCCGAUGCAGCCCGUACCCGGGAGUUCCUGGAAGGCUUCGUGGAUGACUUGCUGGAAGCCCUGAGGAGCCUCUGCAACCGGGACACCGACAUGGAGGUGGAGGACUUCAUUGGCGUGGACAGCAUGUACGAGAACUGGCAGGUGGACAGGCCACUGCUGUGCCACCUUUUCGUGCCCUUCACACCCCCCGAGCCCUACCGCUUCCACCCAGAGCUCUGGUGCUCCGGCCGCUCAGUGCCCCUGGAUCGCCAGGGCUACGGCCAGAUCAAGGUGGUCCGCGCCGAUGGGGACACAUUGAGCUGCAUCUGCGGCAAGACCAAGCUCGGGGAAGACAUGCUGUGUCUCCUGCACGGCAGGAACAGCAUGGCGCCUCCCUGCGGCGACAUGGAGAACCUGCUGUGUGCCACAGAUUCCCUGUACCUGGACACGAUGCAGGUCAUGAAGUGGUUCCAGACGGCCCUCACCAGAGCCUGGAAGGGCAUCGCCCACAAGUACGAGUUCGACCUGGCCUUUGGCCAGCUGGACAGCCCGGGGUCCCUGAAGAUCAAGUUCCGUUCAGGGAAGUUCAUGCCCUUCAACCUGAUUCCUGUGAUCCAGUGUGAUGACUCGGACCUGUACUUUGUCUCCCACCUUCCCAGGGAGCCCUCUGAGGGCACCCCAGCCUCCAGCACAGACUGGCUCCUGUCCUUUGCUGUCUAUGAGCGACACUUCCUCAGGACGACACUAAAGGCACUGCCCGAGGGCGCCUGCCACCUCAGCUGCCUGCAGAUAGCAUCCUUCCUGCUCUCCAAGCAGAGCCGCCUGACCGGUCCCAGCGGGCUCAGCAGCUACCACCUGAAGACGGCCCUACUGCACCUCCUACUCCUCCGGCAGGCCGCCGACUGGAAGGCGGGGCAGCUGGACGCUCGUCUGCACGAGUUGCUGUGCUUCCUGGAGAAGAGCUUGCUCCAGAAGAAGCUCCACCACUUCUUCAUCGGCAACCGCAAGGUGCCUGAGGCCAUGGGACUCCCUGAGGCCGUGCUCAGGGCCGAGCCCCUCAACCUCUUCCGGCCCUUCGUCCUGCAGCGAAGCCUUUACCGUAAGACACUGGACUCCUUCUAUGAGAUGCUCAAGAAUGCCCCAGCGCUCAUUAGCGAGUAUUCCCUACAUGUCCCCUCAGACCAGCCUACCCCAAAAAGCUGACGUCUUUUACAGAAUGUGGGAUCCUCGAGCUAAGAUGAGGGCAUCCCUCACGUUCACACCCCUGGUGGCAUCUGCCAGCCCUGUUCUGGGGACAAGGCGGGCUUUCGUGGGAGCCGUGCUCAGCCUGCCAGGAAGCCAAGCCCUACAGUGCAGAGGAAACAGAAUUUCAACGGGAAGCUGGUUUGCUUCAUACCAUUGGGAUCUGCUGGUAAAGCUGUUAUUUGGGUUUAGGGACUGAUCCCUUGCAGUUUACUUCUGGAUCACCAUGAAUGGCCAAGAUGGUGGCAGAACACGCUGUGGACCCUGAGUUAGAGACAAUGCAAAUGUUGGAUUGGGUGUAAUUCUUUUUGAAUCCCAGAUCCAGUCUGUACUUGAAUAUGAGCAGAGGAUCUACAAGAAUGCUGACAGGGAACCGUGUUAAGACCCAGCACCCCUAUUCCCAGGAGCUUCUGGCCUGACCAUCUGCAGCCAAAGCACUAACAGGGACAGAUAUGGGAAUGUCCACCUUUGAUCCGCAUCCUGCACAAUAGUGGUCCCACCAUGGCUGCCACUUUUUUAUACUAUUUGGAGAAAAGACCUUGUAUAAAUUCGAGGCCCAAAUGACUAACGUCUCUGUCACACGGAAAUGGGUACUUGGUGGCAUAGAGAAACACAAUUAGCCACUUUUUCAGCUACACUUCUCACUCAGCUGCACCCUACACUUCUCACUCAGGUGCACCCCCUUCUGCUGUCCUUUCCCCAACGUACUGGGUCCCGAGCGUGGUGGGUAUUUGCCACACUGGGUGCCAGCUCAGCAGCCCCCCACCUCUCUUUAUUCUCUCCAAAGCUGGUCUUUCUGACUAUCAUUGUGGUAGGGGGAGGACAGAUGCUAAAGGUGGAAGCUGACCUGGAGAAAGAGACACACGGGGUGACUGUGGCAAAGGACAGCUGGAAAAGAAACUCUAUCACUUCUUCAUUGGCAACCACAAGGCACCUGAGGCCAUGGCACUCCCAGAGGCUGUGCGCAGAGCCAAGCCUCUCAACCUCUUCUGGCCCUGCGUCCUGCAGCGAAGUCUCUGCUGUAAGACAGUAGACUCCUUCGAUGAGGUGCUCAAAAAUGCUACCCGGGGUGGUGGUGUCUGGCUUGCAGUCUGGCCCAGUUCAGAGAAAGUUGCAGAGAUCAGGGGCCAAGGAUGUCAUAGCCCCAGGUUGUCCUCAGGGUCCCAAUCCUAGGGCAGGGUGUGCAUGGAAGCAAGAACUAUGGAAACCUAGCUCCAGUCUGCAGGCUCUGAGCCCCUAGUUCCUCACUCCAGCGGGGCUCCCUCACUGCACAGAACCCACCCCUUCUGUGUGGGCACUGCUGACCACACAGAUGACCCAGACCCAAAGAGCCUGGCAGAAGCUCUGUGGUUGGAGCUGGGCUCCGUCUCCAGGUCUGGUUCAGGGGGAUCAGGAAGGCUCUUUUCCACCUGUGGCUUCACUGGCCCUUUGAGAUUUCCUAUCUCACCGUUACUUCAGUUACCCUUGCAGGGGGCCAGGGAGUCAAGAAUAUACCGUGUUCCUCCAGGGUUUAAGCCGGCCAUGCCUUCCCGAGAGCAUAACCAACUUGACAGGGGUGCCCAGUUACCCCACAAACUGAAGGAAGGAGAUCCUUCCCCCAUCCCCAGGAGUGCUCUCAACCAGCCUCAGAAAGCUUGAGAAGAUGGACCCUUUGCCCACCAGGGUUAAUUCCUGGUGGGGCAGCUCGGCUGUGAUCAGGGCAACCAAACCUAUAGGAAGCCUUCCAGUGUGAGCUGGAAUUAGACUGAACAUGUGCUUGGGCCUGCCUCUCCCUAGACGCAGUUGCGGGGCACUCCAGGGAAUGAACCAGCUCAAGUGUGUCCCUAACAGCAGCCUGGAGCUACCCCCAAUCCCUCACAGCCUGACCCUCCUCAUUCCAUCAGAUGCAUUUGUAGAAUCGGGGCAAAUUUCCUUAUUUAUUUAUGGCCCAUGCCUUUCCCCCUCUUCAUCCUGAUCCCGUUUUGCUUUGAAGAGACCCCAGUAACCAAAAAACAGCCUCCAGAAGCCAAAACCAUGCCUGGAUCUCCCAUAGCUUCUCCUUUGCUUCCAGGAGAAAGUUCACUGAAAAAAAAAUAUCUUCUGGCUUCUUGUGUGUACAGAGACAACAGAACUCGGUGGGGAAACGGGAAUCUUUUCUGCACCAAAGCUGCUUCUAAAGCAGAAAGCAGUGGGGCUCUUGGUGUUUCAUGCUGCCUUAUUUAUAUUAAAGGAAGAAUUAAAUCUUGCAAGGAGUAGAAAUGGUCACUGUUUGUUUUUAACUUCAGGAAAUCUGUGAGGCUCCCAGGGCAGAGUUGGGGACAGGGGGGUGGAUUUCCUAUUGACAAAGCAGAAGCUUUCACUCCCUUUUUAUUCUUACACUUUCAGGAGACUUUAAAAAAUAACAAAACAGAACAUUUCUACCCUGUCUUUGAGGCAACUUGUGUGCUGCCCGCAGGGCUCCAGAAAGGGCCUUUGAAAGCUGGCUGUAGGGUGGAUUCCAGCCUAAGACCUUAUUUCACAGAGCUAAUGUCAGCGAGAAAUAUAGGAGCUGGAACUAACAGGAAGCUUUUGGGUUUUAAAGAAAGAGAUUGUAUUUUAAAUAGAGGAUUUUGAGUCCUCUAGGGGACUUUGGCCUUUCCACUAAGGACAACCCUGCCCUCUUUCCCCAGAGUCUCUUUCCCAAGGAUGCUUGACUUUCCCCAGCAACUGCUCACUUGCUUUGCAAAAUAACAAGGGUGAAAUGAAUAGAGUUGGCCCCUAGGCCAAGAGGCUGGUUAUGUUGGGGAAGGGCCUUAUAUCCUCAAAAGCUCUAGCCCCUCUGCAUGCCUGGCUGAAGCACAGCCCCCGUUGAGAACCUGGGGGUGGAGCUCUGGUUCAUCAUCAAGGGUGUCAUCCGAAUCACCCAGACAACCUGGUCCAUUGCCCCGACCCCGCCUUGAACCUACAUGGUGCUCAGAAUCCAGUCUGGAGUGGUCAGGCUAGGCUCGAUUUUUAAAGAUUUCCCCCAAGUGACUGAUGGUACCCCUAGCUGAGGAAGCCCUCUCACUUUCUUUCUUAAUGGAAAGUUAAAGAAAACCCAAGUGGACUACUUUCCCUACAGAUCUAUUGGAAGAUAGAUAGACCUGGGAAAAGCCAAUGAGCCUGCUUGGAAUCUGUGGUCUAAGUGGCAUCAGCUACACCACAAGCUUCUCAUGAGGGCACCCACAUUCACGCUAGUGCCGUAAGCCUCAGAGAGAGGGUGGGAAGGCAUAAGAUGGUGAGCCCUUCUCCCAAGCAGGUCAUGAAUAGUCCACAAGCAUUUGUCAGGAGCCUAACGUGCAUGAGACAUUGUGGAAGAUGGGAAAAUGAAUAGGACCAAGCCUGUUCCCUAGGAGAGGCAGCAGAAGGUGGCCUUCCAAGUACUGAGCUAUUCCAAGUGUGACCCUGCACUACACAUACGGGUGUCACCUGGGGGCAGCUUCCUGGGCCGUGUCACAGACUCCAGUGGGAUCCUGAGAAGUUAGGUAGAAGAAUCUGCACUUCACCAAGUUCCCCACCUGAUUCUGGAUGUCCAAGAACCACUGGUACCUGGGCUGAUUAGGGAAGGCCUCAUGGUGGGGCGCUGCCAGAUAGAGACUCUGAAAAAUGACCAGGACUGUGGCCAGGAAAGACAUUCCAGCCAGAAGCAUGGAGUGAGGGUGGGAAGCACCUACUGUAUGGCAGGCACCGUUCCGCACACACAUUUGUUAAUGCACACAGUUCCAUGUCAGUCCUAUGAUGUAGGUGCUAUUCUUAUCCUCCCUGCUUUCCAGAUAAGGAAACAGGCACUGAAGGGGCAACUGACUUACCUACUGUCACAGUGGUAAGUAGCACAGCCCAGAUUCCAACCCAGGCAGUCCUGGUGUACAUGUUGGCAUAUACUGAGAAGUCGUAGCAAAUGAGGUUGAAAAGAUAAGAGUGGGGCUGAACCAUGCAAAGCCUUGAAUGCUAAUACAAGGUAAAUUUGGACCUCACAACAAGCAGAGGUGGGCCAUUGGCGGGUUUUGAGUGAGACAGUAACUUGAUUCACCCCCAAACUAAGGAGUCCUUAUCUAUGUGAUCAGUGCCAUCCAUGUCCUGUGCUGUAGGGUACAUGGCCGGCUUCCCGAGCAGGGUUGGUGGCAGCUGGCAGUGGUUGGUGAAUGUCCAGGAAGUCUUAACUCAAGCCACCCCAAGGCUGUGAUUCAGAACAUUUUCGUGGUCCGUCUCAUCUCCACCUCACGGGACAGAGCUGGAAGGCUGUUUGGUUUGGCCAGCGACCGAAAGCAGAGGGAGCCAAGAGUCACAGAGUGAAGGGCAAUGUGUGCCUUCAACAGGGCCCUCCCUCUCCGCCCCACUCUGCCUUGCCCCACCCCUGUCCCUGGGAAGGGCAUCUUUUAGAGUUAACUUUUCUCAUUGCCAUCCAAAAAUAGCUUGCUUGUUUAACUAGUUUGUUGUUUAAAAAAUAAACAUAAAAGCAAUAAUACAGUCAUAAUUUUAAAAUUCAAGUACUAACAGGAAAAUUAAGUAACAGACUAACGGUCCCACUUCUGACUUCUUAGUCCACUCCCCAGAGAUAACCAAUAUGAAGUUUUUGGUGUAUCCUUCCAAAAUUUUUCUGUGUAUGUGUCACAUGUAUGUAUAUAUAUAUGCAUCCUUUUAGUCCUUUUUUACAUAAAUGGCAUCAUACCGA